AAUCUUAUGUAUGUAAAACCCCGUUACGAUGUCGGCGACGGGGCCCAUCAGUAACUAUUACGUGGACUCGCUCAUCUCUCACGACAAUGAAGACCUCCUAGCGUCCAGGUUUCCGGCCACCGGGGCUCAUCCCGCCGCCGCCAGACCCAGCGGUUUGGUGCCGGACUGUAGCGAUUUUCCGUCCUGUAGCUUCGCGCCCAAGCCGGCAGUGUUCAGCACGUCGUGGGCGCCCGUGCCCUCUCAGUCGUCCGUGGUAUAUCACCCGUACGGCCCCCAGCCCCACCUCGGCGCCGACACGCGCUACAUGCGGACUUGGCUCGAGCCGCUGUCCGGCGCCGUCUCCUUCCCCAGCUUCCCGGCCGGGGGCCGUCACUACGCCCUCAAGCCGGACGCCUACCCCGGGCGCCGCGCGGACUGCGGCCCAGGGGAGGGCCGCAGCUACCCGGACUACAUGUACGGCUCGCCCGGGGAGCUGCGCGACCGCGCCCCGCAGACACUGCCCUCGCCCGAGGCGGACGCGCUCGCCGGCAGCAAGCACAAAGAGGAGAAGGCCGACCUGGACCCCAGCAACCCCGUGGCCAACUGGAUUCACGCCCGCUCCACGAGGAAGAAGCGCUGCCCCUACACCAAGUACCAGACGCUGGAACUGGAGAAGGAGUUUCUCUUCAAUAUGUAUUUAACCAGGGACCGUCGGUAUGAGGUGGCCCGGGUUCUCAAUCUCACCGAGCGGCAGGUCAAAAUCUGGUUUCAGAAUCGAAGGAUGAAGAUGAAAAAGAUGAAUAAAGAGAAAACCGACAAGGAGCAGUCCUAAACCCUACCCAGCCUGCUGCCUCAGCACAGCCAAGGGAAAAACAAAAACCCCACAAAAUACCCCAACACAGGCGGGGGAGAGACGAAAAAGAAAAGGAAAGAGCAAGAUAGACAAAAGCCAAUCAGCUUAAAAAGAAAAACAAGGAAGGGGAAAAGAAAACUCUUGCGAUUUGGGAGGGUUCAGUGUUGAGAUAUUGGUGUUUUAGAGUUAGUUCUACCCAGCGAGGAGGAGGCGGGGAGAGAAACUGCGUUCUCUUUCCCCAGCGCAACCGAAAUAAAUGACACAUACAAAUGUGAUUUUUUUCCUCCUUUCUUCAGAGAAGCCAGUACUUGAAUCGCUAUAUUUCUAUUUUUUUUUCCCUGUAUCGUAUUUGGUCCAGGUCAUCCCUCCCCGGGCCUGGGGCGCUCUGCGUGCAGAUUUUGUACAAAAAAAAAAAAGACACACACACAUACAUGAUAAUGAUUCCCAGCCCAGGAGCUGAGGGGUGAGGGCUGGGGACCAUGCCGCGGGCUAGGUCGGGCCCGUGCAGGCCGGCGCCUUGGGCUGUACAUAGUGUUCCCUCUCAUCCCCAGGGUUCGUCCCCAGCGUCCGUCCUGUAACGUGCUUCUGUUUGUUAUGGUAGAACAGCCCUGUGUUAAUAUAUUGAAGUCACUUAACCAGAAA